AGCCUGGACACAUAAAUCAGCACGCGGCCGGAGAACCCCGCAAUCUCUGCGCCCACAAAAUACACCGACGAUGCCCGAUCUACUUUAAGGGCUGAAACCCACGGGCCUGAGAGACUAUAAGAGCGUUCCCUACCGCCAUGGAACAACGGGGACAGAACGCCCCGGCCGCUUCGGGGGCCCGGAAAAGGCACGGCCCAGGACCCAGGGAGGCGCGGGGAGCCAGGCCUGGGCCCCGGGUCCCCAAGACCCUUGUGCUCGUUGUCGCCGCGGUCCUGCUGUUGGUCUCAGCUGAGUCUGCUCUGAUCACCCAACAAGACCUAGCUCCCCAGCAGAGAGCGGCCCCACAACAAAAGAGGUCCAGCCCCUCAGAGGGAUUGUGUCCACCUGGACACCAUAUCUCAGAAGACGGUAGAGAUUGCAUCUCCUGCAAAUAUGGACAGGACUAUAGCACUCACUGGAAUGACCUCCUUUUCUGCUUGCGCUGCACCAGGUGUGAUUCAGGUGAAGUGGAGCUAAGUCCCUGCACCACGACCAGAAACACAGUGUGUCAGUGCGAAGAAGGCACCUUCCGGGAAGAAGAUUCUCCUGAGAUGUGCCGGAAGUGCCGCACAGGGUGUCCCAGAGGGAUGGUCAAGGUCGGUGAUUGUACACCCUGGAGUGACAUCGAAUGUGUCCACAAAGAAUCAGGUACAAAGCACAGUGGGGAAGUCCCAGCUGUGGAGGAGACGGUGACCUCCAGCCCAGGGACUCCUGCCUCUCCCUGUUCUCUCUCAGGCAUCAUCAUAGGAGUCACAGUUGCAGCCGUAGUCUUGAUUGUGGCUGUGUUUGUUUGCAAGUCUUUACUGUGGAAGAAAGUCCUUCCUUACCUGAAAGGCAUCUGCUCAGGUGGUGGUGGGGACCCUGAGCGUGUGGACAGAAGCUCACAACGACCUGGGGCUGAGGACAAUGUCCUCAAUGAGAUCGUGAGUAUCUUGCAGCCCACCCAGGUCCCUGAGCAGGAAAUGGAAGUCCAGGAGCCAGCAGAGCCAACAGGUGUCAACAUGUUGUCCCCCGGGGAGUCAGAGCAUCUGCUGGAACCGGCAGAAGCUGAAAGGUCUCAGAGGAGGAGGCUGCUGGUUCCAGCAAAUGAAGGUGAUCCCACUGAGACUCUGAGACAGUGCUUCGAUGACUUUGCAGACUUGGUGCCCUUUGACUCCUGGGAGCCGCUCAUGAGGAAGUUGGGCCUCAUGGACAAUGAGAUAAAGGUGGCUAAAGCUGAGGCAGCGGGCCACAGGGACACCUUGUACACGAUGCUGAUAAAGUGGGUCAACAAAACCGGGCGAGAUGCCUCUGUCCACACCCUGCUGGAUGCCUUGGAGACGCUGGGAGAGAGACUUGCCAAGCAGAAGAUUGAGGACCACUUGUUGAGCUCUGGAAAGUUCAUGUAUCUAGAAGGUAAUGCAGACUCUGCCAUGUCCUAAGUGUGAUUCUCUUCAGGAAGUCAGACCUUCCCUGGUUUACCUUUUUUCUGGAAAAAGCCCAACUGGACUCCAGUCAGUAGGAAAGUGCCACAAUUGUCACAUGACCGGUACUGGAAGAAACUCUCCCAUCCAACAUCACCCAGUGGAUGGAACAUCCUGUAACUUUUCACUGCACUUGGCAUUAUUUUUAUAAGCUGAAUGUGAUAAUAAGGACACUAUGGAAAUGUCUGGAUCAUUCCGUUUGUGCGUACUUUGAGAUUUGGUUUGGGAUGUCAUUGUUUUCACAGCACUUUUUUAUCCUAAUGUAAAUGCUUUAUUUAUUUAUUUGGGCUACAUUGUAAGAUCCAUCUACACAGUCGUUGUCCGACUUCACUUGAUACUAUAUGAUAUGAACCUUUUUUGGGUGGGGGGUGCGGGGCAGUUCACUCUGUCUCCCAGGCUGGAGUGCAAUGGUGCAAUCUUGGCUCACUAUAGCCUUGACCUCUCAGGCUCAAGCGAUUCUCCCACCUCAGCCAUCCAAAUAGCUGGGACCACAGGUGUGCACCACCACGCCCGGCUAAUUUUUUGUAUUUUGUCUAGAUAUAGGGGCUCUCUAUGUUGCUCAGGGUGGUCUCGAAUUCCUGGACUCAAGCAGUCUGCCCACCUCAGACUCCCAAAGCGGUGGAAUUAGAGGCGUGAGCCCCCAUGCUUGGCCUUACCUUUCUACUUUUAUAAUUCUGUAUGUUAUUAUUUUAUGAACAUGAAGAAACUUUAGUAAAUGUACUUGUUUACAUAGUUAUGUGAAUAGAUUAGAUAAACAUAAAAGGAGGAGACAUACAAUGGGGGAAGAAGAAGAAGUCCCCUGUAAGAUGUCACUGUCUGGGUUCCAGCCCUCCCUCAGAUGUACUUUGGCUUCAAUGAUUGGCAACUUCUACAGGGGCCAGUCUUUUGAACUGGACAACCUUACAAGUAUAUGAGUAUUAUUUAUAGGUAGUUGUUUACAUAUGAGUCGGGACCAAAGAGAACUGGAUCCACGUGAAGUCCUGUGUGUGGCUGGUCCCUACCUGGGCAGUCUCAUUUGCACCCAUAGCCCCCAUCUAUGGACAGGCUGGGACAGAGGCAGAUGGGUUAGAUCACACAUAACAAUAGGGUCUAUGUCAUAUCCCAAGUGAACUUGAGCCCUGUUUGGGCUCAGGAGAUAGAAGACAAAAUCUGUCUCCCACGUCUGCCAUGGCAUCAAGGGGGAAGAGUAGAUGGUGCUUGAGAAUGGUGUGAAAUGGUUGCCAUCUCAGGAGUAGAUGGCCCGGCUCACUUCUGGUUAUCUGUCACCCUGAGCCCAUGAGCUGCCUUUUAGGGUACAGAUUGCCUACUUGAGGACCUUGGCCGCUCUGUAAGCAUCUGACUCAUCUCAGAAAUGUCAAUUCUUAAACACUGUGGCAACAGGACCUAGAAUGGCUGACGCAUUAAGGUUUUCUUCUUGUGUCCUGUUCUAUUAUUGUUUUAAGACCUCAGUAACCAUUUCAGCCUCUUUCCAGCAAACCCUUCUCCAUAGUAUUUCAGUCAUGGAAGGAUCAUUUAUGCAGGUAGUCAUUCCAGGAGUUUUUGGUCUUUUCUGUCUCAAGGCAUUGUGUGUUUUGUUCCGGGACUGGUUUGGGUGGGACAAAGUUAGAAUUGCCUGAAGAUCACACAUUCAGACUGUUGUGUCUGUGGAGUUUUAGGAGUGGGGGGUGACCUUUCUGGUCUUUGCACUUCCAUCCUCUCCCACUUCCAUCUGGCAUCCCACGCGUUGUCCCCUGCACUUCUGGAAGGCACAGGGUGCUGCUGCCUCCUGGUCUUUGCCUUUGCUGGGCCUUCUGUGCAGGACGCUCAGCCUCAGGGCUCAGAAGGUGCCAGUCCGGUCCCAGGUCCCUUGUCCCUUCCACAGAGGCCUUCCUAGAAGAUGCAUCUAGAGUGUCAGCCUUAUCAGUGUUUAAGAUUUUUCUUUUAUUUUUAAUUUUUUUGAGACAGAAUCUCACUCUCUCGCCCAGGCUGGAGUGCAACGGUACGAUCUUGGCUCAGUGCAACCUCCGCCUCCUGGGUUCAAGCGAUUCUCGUGCCUCAGCCUCCGGAGUAGCUGGGAUUGCAGGCACCCGCCACCACGCCUGGCUAAUUUUUGUAUUUUUAGUAGAGACGGGGUUUCACCAUGUUGGUCAGGCUGGUCUCGAACUCCUGACCUCAGGUGAUCCACCUUGGCCUCCGAAAGUGCUGGGAUUACAGGCGUGAGCCACCAGCCAGGCCAAGCUAUUCUUUUAAAGUAAGCUUCCUGACGACAUGAAAUAAUUGGGGGUUUUGUUGUUUAGUUACAUUAGGCUUUGCUAUAUCCCCAGGCCAAAUAGCAUGUGACACAGGACAGCCAUAGUAUAGUGUGUCACUCGUGGUUGGUGUCCUUUCAUGCUUCUGCCCUGUCAAAGGUCCCUAUUUGAAAUGUGUUAUAAUACAAACAAGGAAGCACAUUGUGUACAAAAUACUUAUGUAUUUAUGAAUCCAUGACCAAAUUAAAUAUGAAACCUUAUAUAAAAA